ACUCGCGCCCUUGCCGCUGCCACCGCACCCCGCCAUGGAGCGGCCGUCGCUGCGCGCCCUGCUCCUCGGCGCCGCUGGGCUGCUGCUCCUGCUCCUGCCCCUCUCCUCUUCCUCCUCUUCGGACACCUGCGGCCCCUGCGAGCCGGCCUCCUGCCCGCCCCUGCCCCCGCUGGGCUGCCUGCUGGGCGAGACCCGCGACGCGUGCGGCUGCUGCCCUAUGUGCGCCCGCGGCGAGGGCGAGCCGUGCGGGGGUGGCGGCGCCGGCAGGGGGUACUGCGCGCCGGGCAUGGAGUGCGUGAAGAGCCGCAAGAGGCGGAAGGGUAAAGCCGGGGCAGCAGCCGGCGGUCCGGGUGUAAGCGGCGUGUGCGUGUGCAAGAGCCGCUACCCGGUGUGCGGCAGCGACGGCACCACCUACCCGAGCGGCUGCCAGCUGCGCGCCGCCAGCCAGAGGGCCGAGAGCCGCGGGGAGAAGGCCAUCACCCAGGUCAGCAAGGGCACCUGCGAGCAAGGUCCUUCCAUAGUGACGCCCCCCAAGGACAUCUGGAAUGUCACUGGUGCCCAGGUGUACUUGAGCUGUGAGGUCAUCGGAAUCCCGACACCUGUCCUCAUCUGGAACAAGGUAAAAAGGGGUCACUAUGGAGUUCAAAGGACAGAACUCCUGCCUGGUGACCGGGACAACCUGGCCAUUCAGACCCGGGGUGGCCCAGAAAAGCAUGAAGUAACUGGCUGGGUGCUGGUAUCUCCUCUAAGUAAGGAAGAUGCUGGAGAAUAUGAGUGCCAUGCAUCCAAUUCCCAAGGACAGGCUUCAGCAUCAGCAAAAAUUACAGUGGUUGAUGCCUUACAUGAAAUACCAGUGAAAAAAGGUGAAGGUGCCGAGCUAUAAACCUCCAGAAUAUUAUUAGUCUGCAUGGUUAAAAGUAGUCAUGGAUAACUACAUUACCUGUUCUUGCCUAAUAAGUUUCUUUUAAUCCAAUCCACUAACACUUUAGUUAUAUUCACUGGUUUUACACAGAGAAAUACAAAAUAAAGAUCACACAUCAAGACUAUCUACAAAAAUUUAUUAUAUAUUUACAGAAGAAAAGCAUGCAUAUCAUUAAACAAAUAAAAUACUUUUUAUCACAACACAGUACAUAUUUGUCAUUUUUAAAAAGCCACACAAUAGAAACAAGACACCAAGAUAUUUAAUUAUCUUGUUGACUCCUGUAAAAUAGCUAAACACUCAUCAUUCGCGGUGCAAUACUCAUAGACAUAAGUUCCUGAAACAAUAGUUUGCAUGCGUAAGGCAUUCGCACCAAAGAAAUCUGAAAAGAAAAAACAAAUGGUAAUUAGCAGAAUUGUAUUGAAGUGACCCCACUUCUCUACCCCAGAAAAAGACAAAGAUCUGGUACUGUAGAUAAUGAAUAAAUGAGUGGAGCUGAGAACACACA